GUUGCCGCUGCGCACCUGGCUCAGGUGAGCUGCCCCGCCCCCGCCCGGCGCGAGCCCCAGGUCCUGGCAGCAGGUGAGUGGCGGUCGCCAUCAGACCCGCGAAGCCUCUGACCUGUCCAGGUGCCCUGUCCAGCUGACUGCAAGGACAGAGAGGAGUCCUGCCCAGCUCUUGGAUCAGUCUGCUGGCCGAGGAGCCCGGUGGAGCCAGGGGUGACCCUGGAGCCCAGCCUGCCCCGAGGAGGCCCCGGCUCAGAGCCAUGCCAGGUGUCUGUGAUAGGGCCCCUGACUUCCUCUCCCCGUCUGAAGACCAGGUGCUGAGGCCUGCCUUGGGCAGCUCAGUGGCUCUGAACUGCACGGCUUGGGUAGUCUCUGGGCCCCACUGCUCCCUGCCUUCAGUCCAGUGGCUGAAAGACGGGCUUCCAUUGGGAAUUGGGGGCCACUACAGCCUCCACGAGUACUCCUGGGUCAAGGCCAACCUGUCAGAGGUGCUUGUGUCCAGUGUCCUGGGGGUCAACGUGACCAGCACUGAAGUCUAUGGGGCCUUCACCUGCUCCAUCCAGAACAUCAGCUUCUCCUCCUUCACUCUUCAGAGAGCUGGCCCUACAAGCCACGUGGCUGCGGUGCUGGCCUCCCUCCUGGUCCUGCUGGCCCUGCUGCUGGCCGCCCUGCUCUAUGUCAAGUGCCGUCUCAACGUGCUGCUCUGGUACCAGGACGCGUAUGGGGAGGUGGAGAUAAACGACGGGAAGCUCUACGACGCCUACGUCUCCUACAGCGACUGCCCCGAGGACCGCAAGUUCGUGAACUUCAUCCUAAAGCCGCAGCUGGAGCGGCGUCGGGGCUACAAGCUCUUCCUGGACGACCGCGACCUCCUGCCGCGCGCUGAGCCCUCCGCCGACCUCUUGGUGAACCUGAGCCGCUGCCGACGCCUCAUCGUGGUGCUUUCGGACGCCUUCCUGAGCCGGGCCUGGUGCAGCCACAGCUUCCGGGAGGGCCUGUGCCGGCUGCUGGAGCUCACCCGCAGACCCAUCUUCAUCACCUUCGAGGGCCAGAGGCGCGACCCCGCGCACCCGGCGCUCCGCCUGCUGCGCCAGCACCGCCACCUGGUGACCUUGCUGCUCUGGAGGCCCGGCUCCGUGACUCCUUCCUCCGAUUUUUGGAAAGAAGUGCAGCUGGCGCUGCCGCGGAAGGUGCAGUACAGGCCUGUGGAAGGAGACCCCCAGACGCAGCUGCAGGACGACAAGGACCCCAUGCUGAUUCUUCGAGGCCGAGUCCCUGAGGGCCGGGCCCUGGACUCAGAGGUGGACCCGGACCCUGAGGGCGACCUGGGUAUGCCCGCCCAGCCCCACUCCCCAACUGGAGAAGCUCAGCACAGGGCGGAGUGGGGGCAGGCACAGGGCACAGGGCCUGGAGGGGCUCCAGGUGUUGAGGACUCUUCCCGGCACCGGGAGCCCCUGCACGGCCUCUGCCCUGGAGGUGCUCGGCCCUCGGUCUGCCUGGGAACUUCCUGGGCCUCACAGGCCAUCACAGCAGGGGGUGAGCAGGGGCAGCCCCUGGCAGUGGGUCUGGGCCAAGGCUGUGGGUGGCCACCUCAGGCGUCUCGGUCUCCCCACCCCAGGUGUCCGGGGGCCUGUCUUUGGAGAGCCAUCAGCUCCACCGCACACCAGUGGGGUCUCGCUGGGAGAGAGCCGGAGCAGCGAAGUGGACGUCUCGGAUCUCGGCUCGCGAAACUACAGUGCCCGCACAGACUUCUACUGCCUGGUGUCCAAGGAUGAUAUGUAGCUCCCACCCCAGAGUGCAGGAUCAUAGGGACAGCGGGGGCCAGGGCAGCGGCGUCGCUCCUCUGCUCAACAGGACCACAACCCCUGCCAGCAGCCCUGGGACCCUGCCAGCAGCCCUGGGAAAAGGCUGUGGCCUCAGGGCGCCUCCCAGUGCCAGAAAAUAAAGUCCUUUUGGAUUCUG